AGCCCGAAGUUUCCUGCGCCGCGCGCGGACGGGCUCGAGGCUCGCUCGCUGCCUCACCGGUCCCCGGCCCGCGCCCCGCGCCCCGCGCCCCGCGCCCCGGCCUCACCCGUCCGCUCAGCGGCCUCCACGCCGCGCCGAGGCCGCCGCCGUCGCCUCCGCCGGGCGAGCCGGAGCCGGAGUCGAGCCGCGGCCGGGAGCCGGGCGGGCUGGGGACGCGGGCCGGGGGCGGAGGCGCUGGGGGCCGGGGCCGGGGCCGGGGGCGGAGGCGCUGGGGGCCGGGGCCGGGGCCGGGCGCCGAGCGGGGUCCGCGGUGACCGCGCCGCCCGGGCGAUGCCCGCGGGGACGCCGCCGGCCAGCAGAGCGAGGUGCUGCCGGCCGCCACCAUGACCGAGGGCGCACGGGCCGCCGACGAGGUCCGGGUGCCCCUGGGCGCGCCGCCCCCUGGCCCUGCGGCGUUGGUGGGGGCGUCCCCGGAGAGCCCCGGGGCGCCGGGACGCGAGGCGGAGCGGGGGUCCGAGCUCGGCGUGUCACCCUCCGAGAGCCCGGCGGCCGAGCGCGGCGCGGAGCUGGGUGCCGACGAGGAGCAGCGCGUCCCGUACCCGGCCUUGGCGGCCACGGUCUUCUUCUGCCUCGGUCAGACCACGCGGCCGCGCAGCUGGUGCCUCCGGCUGGUCUGCAACCCAUGGUUCGAGCACGUGAGCAUGCUGGUAAUCAUGCUCAACUGCGUGACCCUGGGCAUGUUCCGGCCCUGUGAGGACGUUGAGUGCGGCUCCGAGCGCUGCAACAUCCUGGAGGCCUUUGACGCCUUCAUUUUCGCCUUUUUUGCGGUGGAGAUGGUCAUCAAGAUGGUGGCCUUGGGGCUGUUCGGGCAGAAGUGUUACCUGGGUGACACGUGGAACAGGCUGGAUUUCUUCAUCGUCGUGGCGGGCAUGAUGGAGUACUCGUUGGACGGACACAACGUGAGCCUCUCGGCUAUCAGGACCGUGCGGGUGCUGCGGCCCCUCCGCGCCAUCAACCGCGUGCCUAGCAUGCGGAUCCUGGUCACUCUGCUGCUGGAUACGCUGCCCAUGCUCGGGAACGUCCUUCUGCUGUGCUUCUUCGUCUUCUUCAUUUUCGGCAUCGUUGGCGUCCAGCUCUGGGCUGGCCUCCUGCGGAACCGCUGCUUCCUGGACAGUGCCUUUGUCAGGAACAACAACCUGACCUUCCUGCGGCCGUACUACCAGACGGAGGAGGGCGAGGAGAACCCGUUCAUCUGCUCCUCACGCCGAGACAACGGCAUGCAGAAGUGCUCGCACAUCCCCGGCCGCCGCGAGCUGCGCAUGCCCUGCACCCUGGGCUGGGAGGCCUACACGCAGCCGCAGGCCGAGGGGGUGGGCGCUGCACGCAACGCCUGCAUCAACUGGAACCAGUACUACAACGUGUGCCGCUCGGGUGACUCCAACCCCCACAACGGUGCCAUCAACUUCGACAACAUCGGCUACGCCUGGAUUGCCAUCUUCCAGGUGAUCACGCUGGAAGGCUGGGUGGACAUCAUGUACUACGUCAUGGACGCCCACUCAUUCUACAACUUCAUCUAUUUCAUCCUGCUCAUCAUCGUGGGCUCCUUCUUCAUGAUCAACCUGUGCCUGGUGGUGAUUGCCACGCAGUUCUCGGAGACGAAGCAGCGGGAGAGUCAGCUGAUGCGGGAGCAGCGGGCACGCCACCUGUCCAACGACAGCACGCUGGCCAGCUUCUCCGAGCCUGGCAGCUGCUACGAAGAGCUGCUGAAGUACGUGGGCCACAUAUUCCGCAAGGUCAAGCGGCGCAGCUUGCGCCUCUACGCCCGCUGGCAGAGCCGCUGGCGCAAGAAGGUGGACCCCAGUGCUGUGCAAGGCCAGGGUCCCGGGCACCGCCAGCGCCGGGCAGGCAGGCACACAGCCUCGGUGCACCACCUGGUCUACCACCACCAUCACCACCACCACCACCACUACCAUUUCAGCCAUGGCAGCCCCCGCAGGCCCGGCCCCGAGCCAGGCGCCUGCGACACCAGGCUGGUCCGAGCUGGCGCGCCCCCCUCGCCACCUUCCCCAGGCCGCGGACCCCCCGACGCAGAGUCUGUGCACAGCAUCUACCAUGCCGACUGCCACAUAGAGGGGCCGCAGGAGAGGGCCCGGGUGGCACAUGCCGCAGCCACUGCCGCUGCCAGCCUCAGACUGGCCACAGGGCUGGGCACCAUGAACUACCCCACGAUCCUGCCCUCAGGGGUGGGCAGCGGCAAAGGCAGCACCAGCCCCGGACCCAAGGGGAAGUGGGCCGGUGGACCGCCAGGCACCGGGGGGCACGGCCCGUUGAGCUUGAACAGCCCUGAUCCCUACGAGAAGAUCCCGCAUGUGGUCGGGGAGCAUGGACUGGGCCAGGCCCCUGGCCAUCUGUCGGGCCUCAGUGUGCCCUGCCCCCUGCCCAGCCCCCCAGCGGGCACACUGACCUGUGAGCUGAAGAGCUGCCCGUACUGCACCCGUGCCCUGGAGGACCCGGAGGGUGAGCUCAGCGGCUCGGAAAGUGGAGACUCAGAUGGCCGUGGCGUCUAUGAAUUCACGCAGGACGUCCGGCACGGUGACCGCUGGGACCCCACGCGACCACCCCGUGCGACGGACACACCAGGCCCAGGCCCAGGCAGCCCCCAGCGGCGGGCACAGCAGAGGGCAGCCCCGGGCGAGCCAGGCUGGAUGGGCCGCCUCUGGGUUACCUUCAGCGGCAAGCUGCGCCGCAUCGUGGACAGCAAGUACUUCAGCCGUGGCAUCAUGAUGGCCAUCCUUGUCAACACGCUGAGCAUGGGCGUGGAGUACCAUGAGCAGCCCGAGGAGCUGACUAAUGCUCUGGAGAUCAGCAACAUCGUGUUCACCAGCAUGUUUGCCCUGGAGAUGCUGCUGAAGCUGCUGGCCUGCGGCCCUCUGGGCUACAUCCGGAACCCGUACAACAUCUUCGACGGCAUCAUCGUGGUCAUCAGCGUCUGGGAGAUCGUGGGGCAGGCGGACGGUGGCUUGUCUGUGCUGCGCACCUUCCGGCUGCUGCGUGUGCUGAAGCUGGUGCGCUUUCUGCCAGCCCUGCGGCGCCAGCUCGUGGUGCUGGUGAAGACCAUGGACAACGUGGCUACCUUCUGCACGCUGCUCAUGCUCUUCAUUUUCAUCUUCAGCAUCCUGGGCAUGCACCUUUUCGGCUGCAAGUUCAGCCUGAAGACAGACACCGGAGACACCGUGCCUGACAGGAAGAACUUCGACUCCCUGCUGUGGGCCAUCGUCACCGUGUUCCAGAUCCUGACCCAGGAGGACUGGAACGUGGUCCUGUACAACGGCAUGGCCUCCACCUCCUCCUGGGCCGCCCUCUACUUCGUGGCCCUCAUGACCUUCGGCAACUAUGUGCUCUUCAACCUGCUGGUGGCCAUCCUCGUGGAGGGCUUCCAGGCGGAGGGCGAUGCCAACAGAUCCGACACGGACGAGGACAAGACGUCGGUCCACUUCGAGGAGGACUUCCACAAGCUCAGAGAACUCCAGACCACAGAGCUGAAGAUGUGUUCCCUGGCCGUGACCCCCAACGGGCACCUGGAGGGACGAGGCAGCCUGUCCCCUCCCCUCAUCAUGUGCACAGCUGCCACGCCCAUGCCUACCCCCAAGAGCUCACCAUUCCUGGAUGCAGCCCCCAGCCUCCCAGACUCUCGGCGUGGCAGCAGCAGCUCCGGGGACCCGCCACUGGGAGACCAGAAGCCUCCGGCCAGCCUCCGAAGUUCUCCCUGUGCCCCCUGGGGCCCCAGUGGCGCCUGGAGCAGCCGGCGCUCCAGCUGGAGCAGCCUGGGCCGUGCCCCCAGCCUCAAGCGCCGCGGCCAGUGUGGGGAACGUGAGUCCCUGCUGUCUGGCGAGGGCAAGGGCAGCACCGACGACGAAGCUGAGGACGGCAGGGCCGCGCCCGGGCCCCGUGCCACCCCACUGCGGCGGGCCGAGUCCCUGGACCCACGGCCCCUGCGGCCGGCCGCCCUCCCGCCUACCAAGUGCCGCGAUCGCGACGGGCAGGUGGUGGCCCUGCCCAGCGACUUCUUCCUGCGCAUCGACAGCCACCGUGAGGAUGCAGCCGAGCUUGACGACGACUCGGAGGACAGCUGCUGCCUCCGCCUGCAUAAAGUGCUGGAGCCCUACAAGCCCCAGUGGUGCCGGAGCCGCGAGGCCUGGGCCCUCUACCUCUUCUCCCCACAGAACCGGUUCCGCGUCUCCUGCCAGAAGGUCAUCACACACAAGAUGUUUGAUCACGUGGUCCUCGUCUUCAUCUUCCUCAACUGCGUCACCAUCGCCCUGGAGAGGCCUGACAUUGAUCCCGGCAGCACCGAGCGGGUCUUCCUCAGCGUCUCCAAUUACAUCUUCACGGCCAUCUUCGUGGCGGAGAUGAUGGUGAAGGUGGUGGCCCUGGGGCUGCUGUCCGGCGAGCACGCCUACCUGCAGAGCAGCUGGAACCUGCUGGAUGGGCUGCUGGUGCUGGUGUCCCUGGUGGACAUUGUCGUGGCCAUGGCCUCGGCUGGUGGCGCCAAGAUCCUGGGUGUUCUGCGCGUGCUGCGUCUGCUGCGGACCCUGCGGCCUCUGAGGGUCAUCAGCCGGGCCCCGGGCCUCAAGCUGGUGGUGGAGACGCUGAUAUCAUCACUCAGGCCCAUUGGGAACAUCGUCCUCAUCUGCUGCGCCUUCUUCAUCAUUUUUGGCAUUUUGGGUGUGCAGCUCUUCAAAGGGAAGUUCUACUACUGCGAGGGCCCCGACACCAGGAACAUCUCCACCAAGGCACAGUGCCGGGCCGCCCACUACCGCUGGGUGCGACGCAAGUACAACUUCGACAACCUGGGCCAGGCCCUGAUGUCGCUGUUCGUGCUGUCAUCCAAGGAUGGAUGGGUGAACAUCAUGUACGACGGGCUGGAUGCCGUGGGUGUCGACCAGCAGCCUGUGCAGAACCACAACCCCUGGAUGCUGCUGUACUUCAUCUCCUUCCUGCUCAUCGUCAGCUUCUUCGUGCUCAACAUGUUCGUGGGCGUCGUGGUCGAGAACUUCCACAAGUGCCGGCAGCACCAGGAGGCGGAGGAGGCGCGGCGGCGAGAGGAGAAGCGGCUGCGGCGCCUAGAGAGGAGGCGCAGGAGUAAGGCGCUCCCGGUGGCGGUGGCGGUGGCGGAGGCCCAGCGCCGGCCCUACUAUGCCGACUACUCGCCCACGCGCCGCUCCAUUCACUCGCUGUGCACCAGCCACUAUCUCGACCUCUUCAUCACCUUCAUCAUCUGUGUCAACGUCAUCACCAUGUCCAUGGAGCACUAUAACCAACCCAAGUCGCUGGACGAGGCCCUCAAGUACUGCAACUACGUCUUCACCAUCGUGUUUGUCUUCGAGGCUGCACUGAAGCUGGUAGCAUUUGGGUUCCGUCGGUUCUUCAAGGACAGGUGGAACCAGCUGGACCUGGCCAUCGUGCUGCUGUCACUCAUGGGCAUCACGCUGGAGGAGAUAGAGAUGAGCGCCGCGCUGCCCAUCAACCCCACCAUCAUCCGCAUCAUGCGCGUGCUUCGCAUUGCCCGUGUGCUGAAGCUGCUGAAGAUGGCUACGGGCAUGCGCGCCCUGCUGGACACUGUGGUGCAAGCUCUCCCCCAGGUGGGGAACCUGGGCCUUCUUUUCAUGCUCCUGUUUUUUAUCUAUGCUGCGCUGGGAGUGGAGCUGUUCGGGAGGCUGGAGUGCAGUGAAGACAACCCCUGCGAGGGCCUGAGCAGGCACGCCACCUUCAGCAACUUCGGCAUGGCCUUCCUCACGCUGUUCCGCGUGUCCACGGGGGACAACUGGAACGGGAUCAUGAAGGACACGCUGCGCGAGUGCUCCCGUGAGGACAAGCACUGCCUGAGCUACCUGCCGGCCCUGUCGCCCGUCUACUUCGUGACCUUCGUGCUGGUGGCCCAGUUCGUGCUGGUGAACGUGGUGGUGGCCGUGCUCAUGAAGCACCUGGAGGAGAGCAACAAGGAGGCACGGGAGGAUGCGGAGCUGGACGCCGAGAUCGAGCUGGAGAUGGCGCAGGGCCCCGGGAGUGCACGCCGGGUGGACGCGGACAGGCCUCCCUUGCCCCAGGAGAGUCCGGGCGCCAGGGACGCCCCAAACCUGGUUGCACGCAAGGUGUCCGUGUCCAGGAUGCUCUCGCUGCCCAACGACAGCUACAUGUUCAGGCCCGUGGUGCCUGCCUCGGCGCCCCACCCCCGCCCGCUGCAGGAGGUGGAGAUGGAGACCUAUGGGGCCGGCACCCCCUUGGGCUCCGUUGCCUCUGUGCACUCUCCGCCCGCAGAGUCCUGUGCCUCCCUCCAGAUCCCAUUGGCUGUGUCGUCCCCAGCCAGGAGCGGCGAGCCCCUCCACGCCCUGUCCCCUCGGGGCACAGCCCGCUCCCCCAGUCUCAGCCGGCUGCUCUGCAGACAGGUAGGAGAAGCCGUUGGCCUGCAGCAGAGGCUGGCGGGGAUGGGGGGCUUGCAGGGAUGCCUCGUCUCAUCUGAAGGACCAGCAGACGAGGACAAGGCAGGAGGAGGGUCGCACUGGGUCCUUGGGGCUCCGAAGGUUUCUGCCUGCUGCUUGGUGGAUCUUGGAGCAUUGGGCCCAGGAGGCUGUGCACACCGAUUCCUUGGAAGGGAAGAUUGACAGCCCUAGGGACACCCUGGAUCCUGCAGAGCCUGGUGAGAAAACCCCGGUGAGGCCGGUGACCCAGGGGGGCUCCCUGCAGUCCCCACCACGCUCCCCACGGCCCGCCAGCGUCCGCACUCGUAAGCAUACCUUCGGACAGCGCUGCGUCUCCAGCCGGCCGGCGGCCCCAGGCGGAGAGGAGGCCGAGGCCUCGGACCCAGCCGACGAGGAGGUCAGCCACAUCACCAGCUCCGCCUGCCCCUGGCAGCCCACAGCCGAGCCCCAUGGCCCCGAAGCCUCUCCGGUGGCCGGCGGCGAGCGGGACCUGCGCAGGCUCUACAGCGUGGAUGCUCAGGGCUUCCUGGACAAGCCGGGCCGGGCAGACGAGCAGUGGCGGCCCUCGGCGGAGCUGGGCAGCGGGGAGCCUGGGGAGGCGAAGGCCUGGGGCCCUGAGGCCGAGCCCGCUCUGGGUGCGCGCAGAAAGAAGAAGAUGAGCCCCCCCUGCAUCUCGGUGGAACCCCCUGCGGAGGACGAGGGCUCUGCGCGGCCCUCCGCGGCAGAGGGCGGCAGCACCACACUGAGGCGCAGGACCCCGUCCUGUGAGGCCACGCCUCACAGGGACUCCCUGGAGCCCACAGAGGGCUCAGGCGCCGGGGGGGACCCUGCAGCCAAGGGGGAGCGCUGGGGCCAGGCCUCCUGCCGGGCUGAGCACCUGACCGUCCCCAGCUUUGCCUUUGAGCCGCUGGACCUCGGGGUCCCCAGUGGAGACCCUUUCUUGGACGGUAGCCACAGUGUGACCCCAGAAUCCAGAGCUUCCUCUUCAGGGGCCAUAGUGCCCCUGGAACCCCCAGAAUCAGAGCCUCCCAUGCCCGUCGGUGACCCCCCAGAGAAGAGGCGGGGGCUGUACCUCACAGUCCCCCAGUGUCCUCUGGAGAAACCAGGGUCCCCCUCAGCCACCCCUGCCCCAGGGGGUGGUGCAGAUGACCCCGUGUAGCUCGGGGCUUGGUGCCGCCCACGGCUUUGGCCCUGGGGUCUGGGGGCCCCGCUGGGGUGGAGGCCCAGGCAGAACCCUGCAUGGACCCUGACUUGGGUCCCGUCGUGAGCAGAAAGGCCCGGGGAGGAUGACGGCCCAGGCCCUGGUUCUCUGCCCAGCGAAGCAGGAGUAGCUGCCGGGCCCCACGAGCCUCCGUCCGUUCUGGUUCGGGUUUCUCCGAGUUUUGCUACCAGCCGAGGCUGUGCGGGCAACUGGGUCAGCCUCCCGUCAGGAGAGAAGCCGCGUCUGUGGGACGAAGACCGGGCACCCGCCAGAGAGGGGAAGGUACCAGGUUGCGUCCUUUCAGGCCCCGCGUUGUUACAGGACACUCGCUGGGGGCCCUGUGCCCUUGCCGGCGGCAGGUUGCAGCCACCGCGGCCCAAUGUCACCUUCACUCACAGUCUGAGUUCUUGUCCGCCUGUCACGCCCUCACCACCCUCCCCUUCCAGCCACCACCCUUUCCGUUCCGCUCGGGCCUUCCCAGAAGCGUCCUGUGACUCUGGGAGAGGUGACACCUCACUAAGGGGCCGACCCCAUGGAGUAACGCGCCCGGCCCCGAUGCGAAUCAGGCCUCCCCUACAUCUGGGGGCGUUGGCCGCGAGAUUCCCAUUGACACCUUUGUUUCGUGUGCUUUUAAAUUCAGGUUAAAUGUUGCAAUAAUCUGAUGCAGAAGACUCAGCUUCUCAAGGGAGAGGGAGGGGGCGGAGCGGAAUAAAUAGUAACUUAUUUAAGAAA